GCAGACCGGCCCAGCGACUCUCCCGGGCUGCCAGCCGGGACGCGCGGCCGCCGCCGCUGCAGACGACGAGUCCGCCCUCGUCCCGCGCCCCCGGGGCUCGCGGAGCCAGGUCUCCACCUCUGGGCAGGAGAGUUGCCGACCACCUCGGGGGUGCUUUCUCUGCGCUUGAACAUCUAUAGCUGCUUCUGAGGGGCUGGGAGCCGGGCCCCUGGGAGAGACGAGCCAUGAACCCCCCACAGCCUCUGCAUUUGGGGACCUCACCUUAGGAGAGUGCCAUUUACAGCUUCCGCCAGGGCAAAGGAGCUGAGCAGCCAUCCCAAGCCCAGCCCACCUCCCUCCCCCGGCCCCUGGUAGGCAUGGACUAGCAGCUGUGAGCAGCCAGAGCUGAUGCCCGGCCCCCAGGGGGGCAGAGGCGCCGCCACCAUGAGCCUGGGCAAGCUCUCGCCUGUGGGCUGGGUGUCCAGUUCACAGGGAAAGAGGCGGCUGACUGCAGACAUGAUCAGCCACCCACUCGGGGACUUCCGCCACACCAUGCAUGUGGGCCGUGGCGGGGAUGUCUUCGGGGACACGUCCUUCCUCAGCAACCACGGUGGCAGCUCCGGGAGCACCCAUCGCUCACCCCGCAGCUUCCUGGCCAAGAAGCUGCAGCUGGUGCGGAGGGUGGGGGCGCCCCCCCGGAGGAUGGCAUCUCCCCCUGCACCCUCCCCGGCUCCACCGGCCAUCUCCCCCAUCAUCAAGAACGCCAUCUCCCUGCCCCAGCUCAACCAGGCCGCCUACGACAGCCUCGUGGUUGGCAAGCUCAGCUUCGACAGCAGCCCCACCAGCUCCACGGACGGCCACUCCAGCUACGGCCUGGACUCUGGGUUCUGCACCAUCUCCCGCCUGCCCCGCUCGGAAAAGCCGCAUGACCGAGACCGGGAUGGUUCCUUCCCCUCUGAGCCCGGGCUUCGCCGCUCUGACUCUCUCUUGUCCUUCCGCCUGGACCUCGACCUUGGGCCCUCACUCCUCAGCGAGCUGCUAGGGGUCAUGAGCCUCCCAGAAGCCCCUGCAGCUGAGACUCCAGCCCCCGCUGCAAACCCCCCAGCCCCUACUGCAAACCCCACGGGUCCUGCUGCAAACCCCCCAGCCACUACUGCAAACCCCCCAGCGCCUGCUGCAAACCCCUCAGCACCUGCCGCAACCCCCACGGGUCCUGCUGCAAAUCCCCCAGCCCCUGCCGCAAGCUCCACACCCCAUGGACACUGUCCCAAUGGGGUAACAGCUGGGUUGGGCCCAGUGGCUGAGGUGAAGUCCAGCCCAGUGGGAGGGGGUCCCCGAGGACCUGCUGGCCCUGCCCUCGGCAGGCACUGGGGAGCAGGCUGGGAUGGCGGCCACCACUACCCAGAGAUGGAUGCGCGGCAGGAGCGGGUGGAGGUGCUGCCCCAAGCCCGGGCCUCCUGGGAGAGCCUGGACGAAGAGUGGAGGGCGCCCCAGGCAGGCAGCAGGACCCCAGUGCCCAGCACAGUGCAAGCAAACACCUUUGAAUUUGCGGAUGCUGAGGAGGAUGAUGAGGUCAAGGUGUGAGGGGCUGGGGCACGGUCCCAGGGCCCCACCUAGGUGCAGAGCCGGCCCCUCACCUAACAGCUGGUUCCUACCAGACCGGAGAGGGGAGAAGUCAUGUUGCCCCUAAACCCCUCCCCACCUCUGCAGGACAGACAUGGGAGGGAGGACAGGGAAGGCCAGGCUUGCUCUGGGACUUUUAUGCUCCCAGAGGCCCUGCCAAACUGACCACCUCCCCCGACUGCCACUCUGGACCUAAUAGCUGUUCCUUAGGCCCCACUCCAUGCCACCCCCACCAGCUGGAGGACCCAGCCUCACAGUGUGUCCUUUGUGCCAGACCAAGCGGCCCGUGGGGGGUGGGGGGCAGGGAGUGUACCACACAGGGCCAUUGUCUCACCUCCCAAAGGGACCGCCUGCCCCCAGCUCAUCCCAGAGCGUCCCUGCUGCAACCCUGACAGCCGUCUCCCAGGCCGCUUCCCCAACAUCCCCGCCCCAGCCUCCCUCUUACCCCAGAAAGGUCAGGUAUGACCUCCCGGGGAGGAAUCCCACCUGCCUGUAUACCCCAGACUUGCCUCUGGGGCCUGAUUAAAUAAGGCUGUUUUGAUAAAA